ACACGCUCGGCGCUCGCGGCGGGCGGAAGUGAGGUGCCGGCGGCUGGCGGCCGCGGAGUCUUCGGCGAGACCUACCGGGCCCUGUCUGUGCCGGCCGUGAGCUGCGGCAGGACGGCUGGAGUAAAUCUUGGUGCCAAUAAUGGAACGAACACUGGACACAGGACUGGGGAAGACUGGAUUUCAGCUUAGGAGAAGAAUACUAAGAAGUUUCAGCAGUGGAAUGCCUACUCUUCUUAUAACCGGAGUGGAAACGGAAGCAUUUUGUGAGAGGGCUGGAGGGAAGAUUACUUCUCUAACAGGAUCACCAGUUUGCUCCACAAAGCACAAUGUCUCGAUCACGACAACCCCCCCUUGUGACCGGCAUCUCUCCAAAUGAAGGGAUACCAUGGACGAAGGUCACAAUCAGGGGAGAAAAUCUGGGGACUGGCCCCACCGACCUCAUAGGCUUGACCAUUUGUGGACAUAAUUGCCUCCUGACGGCAGAAUGGAUGUCUGCAAGUAAAAUAGUAUGUCGAGUGGGACAAGCCAAAAAUGACAAAGGAGACAUUAUUGUCACCACUAAGUCAGGUGGCAGAGGAACCUCAACAGUCUCUUUCAAGCUACUCAAACCUGAGAAAAUAGGCAUUUUGGAUCAGUCUGCUGUGUGGGUUGAUGAAAUGAAUUAUUAUGAUAUGCGCACUGACAGGAACAAAGGAAUUCCGCCCUUGUCCUUACGUCCUGCUAACCCGCUUGGCAUUGAGAUUGAAAAAAGUAAAUUUUCGCAGAAGGACUUAGAAAUGCUAUUCCAUGGAAUGAGUGCUGAUUUUACAAGUGAGAAUUUCUCAGCAGCCUGGUAUCUUAUAGAGAAUCACUCAAACACCAGUUUUGAGCAGCUCAAAAUGGCAGUCACCAACCUAAAGAGACAGGCUAACAAGAAGAGUGAGGGCAGCCUGGCCUAUGUGAAAGGCGGUCUCAGUACAUUCUUCGAAGCACAGGAUGCCCUCUCAGCCAUCCAUCAAAAACUAGAAGCAGAUGGAACGGAAAAAGUAGAAGGAUCCAUGACGCAGAAACUGGAGAAUGUUCUGAACAGAGCAAGUAAUACUGCAGACACAUUGUUUCAAGAAGUAUUAGGUCGGAAAGACAAGGCAGAUUCCACUAGAAAUGCACUCAAUGUGCUUCAGCGAUUUAAGUUUCUUUUCAACCUUCCUCUAAAUAUUGAAAGGAAUAUUCAAAAGGGUGAUUAUGAUGUGGUUAUUAAUGAUUAUGAAAAGGCCAAGUCACUUUUUGGGAAAACGGAGGUGCAAGUUUUCAAGAAAUAUUAUGCUGAAGUAGAAACAAGGAUUGAAGCUUUAAGAGAAUUACUUCUGGAUAAAUUGCUUGAGACACCAUCAACUUUACAUGACCAAAAACGUUACAUAAGGUACCUGUCUGACCUUCAUGCGUCUGGUGACCCUGCUUGGCAAUGCAUUGGAGCCCAACACAAGUGGAUCCUUCAGCUCAUGCACAGUUGCAAAGAGGGCUACGUGAAAGAUCUGAAAGGUAACCCAGGCCUGCACAGUCCCAUGUUGGAUCUUGAUAAUGAUACACGUCCCUCAGUGUUGGGCCAUCUCAGUCAGACAGCGUCCCUGAAGAGGGGCAGCAGCUUUCAGUCUGGUCGAGACGACACGUGGAGAUACAAAACUCCCCACAGGGUGGCCUUUGUUGAAAAAUUGACAAAACUCGUCUUGAGCCAGCUGCCUAACUUCUGGAAACUCUGGAUCUCCUACGUUAAUGGAAGCCUCUUCAGUGAGACUGCUGAGAAGUCAGGCCAGAUUGAAAGAUCAAAGAAUGUAAGGCAAAGACAAAAUGAUUUUAAGAAAAUGAUUCAGGAAGUAAUGCACUCCCUGGUGAAGCUUACCCGCGGAGCCCUGCUUCCCCUCAGCAUCCGGGAUGGGGAAGCCAAGCAGUACGGAGGCUGGGAGGUGAAGUGCGAGCUCUCCGGACAGUGGCUCGCUCACGCCAUCCAGACUGUAAGACUUACUCAUGAAUCGUUGACUGCCCUUGAAAUUCCUAAUGACCUGUUACAGACUAUCCAGGAUCUCAUCUUGGAUCUCCGAGUACGUUGCGUAAUGGCCACGUUGCAGCACACGGCGGAAGAAAUAAAGAGAUUAGCUGAAAAAGAAGACUGGAUUGUUGACAAUGAAGGACUGACUUCUCUACCAUGUCAGUUUGAACAGUGCAUCGUGUGUUCUCUGCAGUCACUGAAGGGGGUUCUGGAGUGCAAGCCGGGAGAGGCCAGUGUCUUCCAACAACCUAAAACACAGGAGGAGGUUUGCCAGCUAAGCAUCAAUAUAAUGCAGGUUUUUAUAUACUGUCUGGAACAGUUGAGCACCAAGCCUGAUGCAGAUAUAGAUACUACACAUCUCUCUGUUGAUGUUUCUUCCCCUGACUUGUUUGGAAGUAUCCAUGAAGACUUCAGCUUGACCUCAGAACAGCGCCUUUUGAUAGUCCUAAGUAAUUGCUGCUAUCUAGAACGUCACACCUUCCUAAAUAUCGCAGAACAUUUUGAAAAGCACAACUUCCAGGGAAUAGAAAAAAUCACACAGGUUAGCAUGGCCUCAUUGAAAGAACUAGAUCAAAGACUCUUUGAAAAUUACAUCGAGUUGAAAGCAGAUCCCAUCGUUGGCUCCUUAGAACCUGGAAUUUAUGCAGGAUAUUUUGAUUGGAAGGACUGCCUGCCUCCAACAGCCAAGGAAACUGAAGUCCAGACGAAACACUGUCUACAGCCGUCAAGGAGCAUUUGGUUGACAAACUGGGACUUCUGCCUCUGCCUCCUAACACUUUUCAAAAGUAUAUCAUUUUUCAGCAAGCUAAUCAAUGUGCUUAAACUCUACAUUGUAUCAAGAGUCUAAAAAUAGUACAAUUAGCAUAAAAAGCUCAGUUUGUGGCUAGAUUUUUAAGUGUGUGGAGCAAGAGACAUCAACAAAGCAGUUUGUGUCUAUGGGAGCAAAUUAAAGGCAAUGUUAUUAAAAUCCUUAUAUUGCAGAGGAUAUUUACUUGAGACUUAGAUUCUUUUUGUAUCAAUUUACUUCAGUUUUCUCAUAAUAUCACAUACUAAUAAUCAAAAUGUUUGAGUGACAACCAGAGUAAAUUCAUAAAUGUAAUAUAUCUGAAAACCCAUUUUUCUUUUUUGAAAUUGCUGUCAUUUCUGGUUGCAAAUGGUGUGACAGCCUAUGAUUACAGUAAUAGGGACUUUAAGGAUUAUACAUAGAAUGCAUGUGACUUUUAGCAAGUUUGUGUAUUGAAGGAAUUUAAUAAGAGGUUUUAUGGAAUCACAAAAGCUACCUUCAUGGACUUUAAAUAUGAUGGAUAUGAAAGAAACUAAUAUUCUUGUACUCUACGGUCGGGUUGUAUUAAUGAAAAGAAAAAUUGGUGUGUGUGCUUGGACUUUCGUUUCUUCUCAUUUUCCUCCUUGGUUUGUGCUGGGGCUUCCUUUUUCAUAUUCUGCUAAGGAAAACAGGUUCGGCAGAUCAUUUAGCCUCACUGGGGCUGUGCUGCUCGUGGACACGUGGGCCGUGUGCAGCCGCACUGCACGUAAACCGUGGGUGACCACGCCGUGCUCUUGGUACGGCACGUGGUCUGGCUCUUCCCCACGGGGACUGGAGCACACUGAAGAUAACACACAUGCAGUGACCCAGUUCCAUUCCAGCCUGUGACCCAAGAGAAUGAGUGUUUAUGCCCGCCAAAAGACACCACCAGCUGCAUUCAUAACGGCUCUGCUGGAAAUACCUGAAAAUGGGAGCUGGGAAACAUAGAGUCGCAGAGUCGGCCUAUUUUGUGGGGUUUAAGCGUCCAUUGUUGAAAAUAAAAUGCCAGACGACAUUUUGCUUUGGUUCAUAUUGAAAACCUCAUGGAUUUAUUCAGGUAUUUCAUUUGGUCCAUUUUCAAAUGAAAAUAUUUUACAGUUUACUUACUGCUUUCACAUACAUUCUUGUAUGUUAUCUUCACACCAACCGUGUUGGGGUUAGAUACUGUUUUCCCCAUGUGGCAAAUUUUUAAAAUUUGGAGAAUCAAGAAAGGCUGUGUAACUUGCUCAAAUAAGGGAACUAGGCCCAACUUUUCAUCUCCAAUUCUAACUUUAUCACUCUUACCAAGAAACAUGUACAGGGCAUGGGUCAGACCACGGGGCUAACAAUACGGUGUCGUUUUGUAUAUCUUCAUGUUUGUAAAUACAGCAGACCCCUGUACGACAGAUAGUUGGGGUGCCAACCUGCUGUACAGUCUGAAAUCUUUGUUUACCCCCAGAAUUUAACUAGGAAUAGCCUGCUGUUGCCCAGAUGACUUAUUAAUAACAUAAACAGUCUGUUACAUAUUUUACGUAUAUACUAUAUUCUGUAUUCUUAAAGUAAGCUAGAGAAAAGAAAAUGCUAUUAAGAAAAUCAUAAGAAAGGAAAAUACAUUUACUACUCAUGAAGUGGAAGUGGAUCAUCAUAAAGGUCUUCAUCCUCAUCUUCACAUUGAGUAGGCUGAGGAGGAAGAGGAGGAUCGGAGCUGGUUUAGCUGUGUCAGGGGCAGCAGAGGCAUGAGAAAACCCACCUAUGGGUGGACCCACGCGGUUCAAACCUGUAUUGUUCGUGGACCAACUGGAAUUGAGUUUGCAAAGUACUGUGGGCCUUCCUCAGUCCCAGGUGCUGUUAACAGAGCUGAGAAGGGGCUCAAGGACCAUGGCCUGGUGGCCCUCCCCUGCUGACAAAAGGGCAGUGGCUUAACCCCAAGGAAGAAGACUGUGUGUGUAUAUGCACCUUGCCCUUCUGACAAACACCAACCCAUGAGGGAGAGUUUCCAAGUAUGGCAAAGCUGUGAAUGAACGAUAAAGAUACCAGGAAGAGUAAAGGGGUUGCACUUAUUUUUGGAUAAAGCAUCUGCACAACAGUGUACCAGGCACGAAGCAACAGAUGUGGCGGAGUGAUGCGAGUGAUCAUUGAUACUGAAGACGGGAGAACAGAUGAGUCAUUGCUAAUAGAAUCUCAAGAGAAAUAACAAGCAACAUGGAAUUCAGUAUUUGAAUGAGAUUUUCUUAGAAAAAGAAACAAGUCUAUGAAACGAGGCACUGUUCCUGCCCUUGCUGCCCUGAGCCUGUGGGCCUCAUUGGUGACAUCCUUGGAGUGCACUCUAAGCUGGCCUUGCAGCUUUAGAAACGCAGGCCCCUGCAGGUGAGCGGCUUGUCCCGCUCGGGCUGGGUUCAAUCCAGAUGCCCCCGUGCAGCCCUCUCUUGGCCUCACACUUCAAUGUCGUCAGUCCCAACAGGGUGCAAGGCCAGUGCUUUGUGGUUUUAGCCAUCUAAACAGAUGUGUGGCAUAUUCAAAAAUUAGUCUCCUUAAAUGUAUGCAUUUCUACCUAGAUUUCUUACUCUGUAAAUGGGACUUUAAAAUCCCAGUUAGCAAUUGGGUUUUCAUAUUUUUUUUUUGCCUUCCAUUUUAUUAUGACUCAAAAUUGUUUUUAAUUUCAAGGUGUUUUCUUUUUGGAAGGUUUUACGGCUAUUUCUUCAAUUGCAUAUGGACCCCCGCUAUAUUGAGAAUAGGAGCUAUACCCUAUUACUUCUUUCCCGUGCUCCACGGUAAUGACUGCAGUCAAAGGGGUGCGGGACCCGCUCAGCAGCAGGCACGGCACUGCCUGGCAUUUUGCACCAUCUUGCGUGCCAGGCCAUGGCAGGAACCCUUCCCAGCAUUCACUCGUGUAGCCACAGGGACCACGCAGGAAAAUAGGGGUCAGGACCCCAGCUGCUUCCAGACCUGCUUCUCUCAUAGCAGUCAUUGGUUUUGAUCUCAGCUCAUUAAAAUCUUUAAAAACAAAAACAAAACACCUUCUUGAAAUUGUGAAAAUCAACAGUUAACCCAGGCCUGUUUAUGAAGUAGUAUGUCCAGAAGUAACACCUCACAGUGCAAAACAAACGCAUUCAUCUGCAUGUAUAGAAUGAAUCCUGUUUUCUUGUCACUUUCACUUUUCUAACUGAAGUUUCCUUGUAAUGAAAAAAAAAUUUCUGACAAAAAACUAAAUUCAAACAAAUGGUUUGUCUGUUUAUAUUAAGUUAAUUAACUUUCUACCUUUAUGUCUAAAAUUCAGUGUAUCAAGUUUGUGAAACGUAUUCUAUGCUAAGUGUGUAAUGAGUUCUGUGACAUCUUAUGUUAGGAUAAUUCAUGGUCUGUUCUACACAUCAGACUUUACAUUUUGAAAUGAGAGGGGAGAGUUUUUUCCACUUGCGUAUAUUUGAGUCUUGAAAGCUGUUUGUCUAUGAAGUUUAUGAAUCUAAACUCUUAUGAAUAUAAAGUCUUUCUUACAGAUGGGAAAAAAUAAACCAUGUAACCAUUUCACUGUUAUUUUCACUGUUGGCAAUGUUUUCUCUUUUCUCGAGGAAAGAGUUUUCCUAUUGAGAUUGAUCACGCUGAUCAAUAAGAGAUCCUACUGAUGAAAGCAAUGAAAAAAAAAAUCCUGGGAUGGAAAACAGAAAGCAGGAGAGGGCGAAGGUACCCAUUCAUGUGCUACAUAGGAAGGGUGUCCUUUCCUCAAAUAGUCAUUGAAAAAAUCCACUUUAGGGCAAAAGACAUUUAUCAAUUUGGGAAUGAGGGCACUAAAACCUGACGAAGGGGAACUUAAAACUCUUUAGUUAGUCCAACAAGAGCUGAUUUUGCUGCAGAAUGGUUAGGACUUUCUCUCUGUUCUACUAAUAGUGAUACAGUUUCUGGUUAUCUUUUUCUUUUUUUUAAUUAGGCAGUAAUUUCGAUAAUGUGUGUUCAGAGUGUAAUUGAAUAGAUAAUUCACUUGAAAAAAAUACACCAAAGUUUUUUCAGUAGUGUUUCAGUUUGACAAUAAAAAAAAGUACAUUGUGGGAUAUUUAUAGUAUUUUUGAAUCUAUUUUUACCAGUAGACUGGGAGUGAUAACUGAUUUGGGGCAUAGGGGUUAAAAACAGGAAAUGUGGUUUAUACAGUAGGUAGUAUCUCCAGAGUUUCCAGGGUUGAUUUCUUAUAGUAUUGUCUGAAGAGUGUUAUGCGUCAAAACAACAUUAGGCCGAGUACCUUGAAAUCCGCCUGUGUUUAAAGGAGCCGUCUUUCCAAUUACAACAGGAAAUGCUUCAUGGAAAAGUUUGCAUUCUUGGUAUAGGUUAAGAUGGCAUAGCAGUUGUUUAUUGUAAUUACAACACGUUCUUCCUCUCCAGCACUUUUCAGACACUUUUUAUACAGUCAGAGUAAAUCUUGUGUCACUUCUAGUAAAUUUCCUUCAAUUUUCGUAUUAAAAUUUUAUUUUAUUUUCAUGAAAAGUUUUGUCAAAUAGCUGUUAAGAAUGUUUUAAAAUAGACUAUCAUAGCUGAGGAGGAGCAUAUAUUAGGGAUACUGUUAAUUACAGUAAUCAGAGAAUCCAAGUUAAGAGGAUAAAAAGGCAUGAAGAAAUAGGAGUAUAAUUCUGUGUGGCCUUUUGCAUGAUAGGUUGGCAGAAUCCAUGAAAACUGAAUAGCUUGAUUACCUUUGCACUCAGCAAUUCCACUUCUGGGAAGAUAUCUUACAUAAACUGUUGUAUUAGAAUCCAAGAAUCUAUGUUUAUUGCAGCAUUAUUUAUGGUAGUAAAUUGAAAGGCAACAUAAGUUCCCCAUAGUAGGAGAAUGGUCAAAUAGAUUAUGAUACAUCCAUGCUAGAAUACUAAGCAGCCAUCAAAAAUUAUAAGGUAGAUACGUAUGCACUGAAGAGCAAACAGGUUGUUUGCUUAAGUCAAAGACCUUCACAGACAACUUACCAAAGUAAAUAUGCAGAUGGAGAAUAAGCAUAUGAAAAGAUGUUCCACAUUGUGUGUCAUUAGGGAAUUGCAAAUUAAAACAACAGUAAGAUACCAUUGCACACCUAGUAGAAUGGCCAAAAUCCAGAACACUGAAAACACCAACUGCUGGUGAGCAUGUGGAGCACCAGGAUCUCUCCUUCAUUGCUAGUGGGACUACAGAAUUACCCAGCCACUUUGGAAGACAGUUUGGCAGCCUCUUACGAAACUAGACAUCCUCUUACCAUAUAAUCCAUGAUUGGCACCACUUGGCAUUUAGCCAAGGGAGUGGAAAAGUUACAUCCACACAAAAACCUGCACACCAAUGCUUGUAGCAAUCUUAUUCAUAAUUGCCAAAACUUGGAAGCAACCAAGUAAUCCUUCAGUAGGUGAAUAAAUGUGUUACGGUCCAUCUGGAAAAUGAAUAUUACUCGGCACUAAGAUGAAAUGAGCAAGGCAUGGAAGGAACCUUAAAUGCAUGUUACUAAGUGAAAUAAGAUAAACUGAAAAGGCUGCAUAUUGUGUGAUUCCAACUAUACGACACUCUGUAACAGGAGAAACUAUGGAGAGAUUAAAAAGAUCAGUGGUUGUCGGGGGUUACUGGGGAAGGAGGGAGCACAGAGGAGUUUUAGGGCAGUGAAGCUACUGUGUGUGUUACCGUAACGGUUGGUACCUGUCGUUAUAUAUUUGUCCAAACCUGUAACAUGUACACCACCAAAAUUGACCCUAAUGUAAACUGUGGAAUUUGGGUAAUAAUGACACAUGUCAGUGUAGGUCUUUCGACUGUAACAAAUGCACCCCUCUGGUGGGGAUGCUGACAGUUGGGGCGGCCGUGUGUAUGUGGUGGCGGGCGGGACGGCAUAUGUGAAAUCUCUGCACCUUCUGCUCAGUUUUGCUGUGAAACUCAAACUGCUCUAAAAAGUAUAGUCAAUUAAAAAAUUGUUAUAGAUUACAGAAUGAAAUUUAGCAAGUUUCAAGAAGAGAAUGUGUAACAUCUCAUUUUUUAGGAAAAAAAUAUAUUCAUAGGAAAAGAUCUGGAAGAACAUACACUAACCUGUCAAUAGUGGUUAUUCCUAAGAAGGAUGAAAGAGGAGUUUAUUGGGCAACUGUGUUCUUUACAAUGAGCAUUUAAUUACUCAGUUUUCUGAAUAAAAAAUUAAGGACGAA